ACCAUCUCCCACUCCUGCAGCUCUUCUCACAGGACCAGCCACUAGCGCAGCCUCGAGCGAUGGCCUAUGUCCCCGCACCGGGCUACCAGCCCACCUACAACCCGACGCUGCCUUACUACCAGCCCAUCCCGGGCGGGCUCAACGUGGGAAUGUCUGUUUACAUCCAAGGAGUGGCCAGCGAGCACAUGAAGCGGUUCUUCGUGAACUUUGUGGUUGGGCAGGAUCCGGGCUCAGACGUCGCCUUCCACUUCAAUCCGCGGUUUGACGGCUGGGACAAGGUGGUCUUCAACACGUUGCAGGGCGGGAAGUGGGGCAGCGAGGAGAGGAAGAGGAGCAUGCCCUUCAAAAAGGGUGCCGCCUUUGAGCUGGUCUUCAUAGUCCUGGCUGAGCACUACAAGGUGGUGGUAAAUGGAAAUCCCUUCUAUGAGUACGGGCACCGGCUUCCCCUACAGAUGGUCACCCACCUGCAAGUGGAUGGGGAUCUGCAACUUCAAUCAAUCAACUUCAUCGGAGGCCAGCCCCUCCGGCCCCAGGGACCCCCGAUGAUGCCACCUUACCCUGGUCCCGGACAUUGCCAUCAACAGCUGAACAGCCUGCCCACCAUGGAAGGACCCCCAACCUUCAACCCGCCUGUGCCAUAUUUCGGGAGGCUGCAAGGAGGGCUCACAGCUCGAAGAACCAUCAUCAUCAAGGGCUAUGUGCCUCCCACAGGCAAGAGCUUUGCUAUCAACUUCAAGGUGGGCUCCUCAGGGGACAUAGCUCUGCACAUUAAUCCCCGCAUGGGCAACGGUACCGUGGUCCGGAACAGCCUUCUGAAUGGCUCGUGGGGAUCCGAGGAGAAGAAGAUCACCCACAACCCAUUUGGUCCCGGACAGUUCUUUGAUCUGUCCAUUCGCUGUGGCUUGGAUCGCUUCAAGGUUUACGCCAAUGGCCAGCACCUCUUUGACUUUGCCCAUCGCCUCUCGGCCUUCCAGAGGGUGGACACAUUGGAAAUCCAGGGUGAUGUCACCUUGUCCUAUGUCCAGAUCUAAUCUAUUCCUGGGGCCAUAACUCAUGGGAAAACAGAAUUAUCCCCUAGGACUCCUUUCUAAGCCCCUAAUAAAAUGUCUGAGGGUGUCUCA